AAUUUCCACUCCCCCCACCCCACUUCGCCUGCCGCGGUCGGGUCCGCGGCCUGCGCUGUAGCGGUCGCCGCCGUUCCCUGGAAGUAGCAACUUCCCUACCCCACCCCAGUCCUGGUCCCCGUCCAGCCGCUGACGUGAAGAUGAGCAGCUCAGAGGAGGUGUCCUGGAUUUCCUGGUUCUGUGGGCUCCGUGGCAAUGAAUUCUUCUGUGAAGUGGAUGAAGACUACAUCCAGGACAAAUUUAAUCUUACUGGACUCAAUGAGCAGGUCCCUCACUAUCGACAAGCUCUAGACAUGAUCUUGGACCUGGAGCCUGAUGAAGAACUGGAAGACAACCCCAACCAGAGUGACCUGAUUGAGCAGGCAGCCGAGAUGCUUUAUGGAUUGAUCCACGCCCGCUACAUCCUUACCAACCGUGGCAUCGCCCAGAUGUUGGAAAAGUACCAGCAAGGAGACUUUGGUUACUGUCCUCGUGUGUACUGUGAGAACCAGCCAAUGCUUCCCAUUGGCCUUUCAGACAUCCCAGGUGAAGCCAUGGUGAAGCUCUACUGCCCCAAGUGCAUGGAUGUGUACACACCCAAGUCAUCAAGACACCAUCACACGGAUGGCGCCUACUUCGGCACUGGUUUCCCUCACAUGCUCUUCAUGGUGCAUCCCGAGUACCGGCCCAAGAGACCUGCCAACCAGUUUGUGCCCAGGCUCUACGGUUUCAAGAUCCAUCCGAUGGCCUACCAGCUGCAGCUCCAAGCCGCCAGCAACUUCAAGAGCCCAGUCAAGACGAUUCGCUGAUUCCCUCCCCCACCUGUCCUGCAGUCUUUGACUUUUCCUUUCUUUUUUGCCACCCUUUCAGGAACCCUGUAUGGUUUUUAGUUUAAAUUAAAGGAGUCGUUAUCGUGGUGGGAAUAUGAAAUAAAGUAGAAGAAAAGGCCA